AGUUCUGCGGUUUCUGCGGCGGCUGGAGAGGUGGUCGGAGAAGUAGGAACCUCCUGCCGGGCUCGUGGCGGCUUCUGUCCGCUCCGCGGAGGGAAGCGCCUUCCCCACAGCUUGUUGUUUGAAGUCUGCCUUCCAACUUUCUUCGUGCGAACUCCGACAAAAGGAACGAAUUUUAAACUUGGUGGUUUAAUCAAAAAAUGCUAGGACGAGUUACUUCCGAAUUUGACUUCUAAUUUUCUGAACUGCAAAACAAGAAGGGAACAAUAAAUUUCUGUGGCUGAUACCACAUCUAAAAGAUUAGAACACUUAACAAGGAAUUUUUAAAGAAUGACAUCAAUGCAAGCUUGAAUAAGAAAAACAAAUUCUUCCUCCUAAGCCAUGGCAUAUCAGUUAUACAGAAAUACUACUUUGGGAAACAGUCUUCAGGAGAGCCUAGAUGAGCUCAUACAGUCUCAACAGAUCACCCCCCAACUUGCCCUUCAAGUUCUACUUCAGUUUGAUAAGGCUAUAAAUGCAGCACUGGCUCAGAGGGUCAGGAACAGAGUCAAUUUCAGGGGCUCUCUAAAUACGUACAGAUUCUGCGAUAAUGUGUGGACUUUUGUACUGAAUGAUGUUGAAUUCAGAGAGGUGACAGAACUUAUUAAAGUGGAUAAAGUGAAAAUUGUAGCCUGUGAUGGUAAAAAUACUGGCUCCAAUACUACAGAAUGAAUAGAAAAAAUAUGACUUUUUUACACCAUCUUCUGUUAUUCAUUGCUUUUGAAGAGAAGCAUAGAAGAGACUUUUUAUUUAUUCUAGAAUUGCAGAAAUGACUACACUGUGCUAUACCAGAGAAUUCCAGUAGAAAGAAACUUGUAACUCUGUAGCCUCUUACAUCACCUUUAUUAUACAGCAUGAAAAACCAUAACUUUUUUUUAAGGACAAAAGUUGUUGCCUUCCUAAGAACCUUCUUUAAUAAACUCAUUUUAAAACUCUGAGUAAUAACUGGUGAAGCUAUUAAGGUAGCAAUAUGAAGAUAUUAGAUAAUGCAUUUUCCCAUUUCCUUUGCAAGGAACAUGAUGCCCUUUCAGAAUGCUUAUUUCAAUAAAGUCAUGUUUUGUCAGUUGUAACUUUACCUGAUGAAAGCAUCAGCAGGGGCAAAACCAAACUCUGGAUGGAAUUUUUUAAGAAAAUCCCUUGCUUUUUAAAAUACAAAACCAAAGUUAAUCAUUGGUAUAAAAAAACCCAAGUACAACUUGAUUAGGAAAAGUUAGACAAUCAUAGCAAAAACAAAACCAAAAAACUUUCCUUCUUAGACCAGGUAACAUGAGGAAGGGGGAAAAAAACCCAAACAAAAUAGUCCCCCCACAUGACAGGUGUCUUCAGCUUGCCAUAUUGAUCCAAAGUUCAUACAUUUUAUCAUGUACAAGAUACAUUAGACUUACAAUAAAGUCUAAUUAUUAGACUUUUAUGUCAGUGGAUUGUGCUUGCAGAAAUACAGAAGUAACAUACUGACCCUAGGUGAGGAGUUUCUUACAUGGUUAACUGGAUUGACCCAAUUGGAGUAAAAGAUUUUUGCUGUUACCUCGAUGCUCCUGCAGUUGUUACCUCAGCAUGCCACUGUAGUCCUUGACUCUCACAUUAAAACUAACUUUGGCUAGGUACUGGUGGCUCACACCUGUAAGUAAUCCCAGUACUUUAGGAGGCUGAGACUGGAGGAUUACUUGAGUCCAGGAGUUGGAGACCAGCCUGGCCAAUAUAGACUGUCCCUACAAAGAAAAUAAAAUUGUUUCAUCUUCCAA